GCCAGAGCCUCAAGCUUCGCUGCUGGGCAGUUGGCUGGAGGGGCUGCUGCUGGGAACACCUGGAGUCUCCGCGGGCAGAUCUCAUAUUUUGGAUUCUGGAUAUAUUAUAAUGAGUGACACUUUGACAGCGGAUGUCAUUGGUCGAAGAGUUGAAGUUAAUGGAGAACAUGCAACAGUACGUUUUGCUGGUGUUGUCCCUCCCGUGGCAGGACCCUGGUUAGGAGUAGAAUGGGACAAUCCCGAGAGAGGAAAGCAUGAUGGGAGCCACGAAGGGACUGUGUAUUUUAAAUGCAGGCACCCGACAGGAGGAUCCUUUAUUCGUCCGAACAAGGUAAAUUUUGGAACAGACUUUCUUACUGCAAUUAAGAACCGCUAUGUGUUAGAAGAUGGACCAGAGGAAGAUAGAAAAGAGCAAAUUGUUACAAUUGGAAAUAAACCUGUGGAGACUAUCGGUUUUGACUCUAUUAUGAAACAGCAAAGUCAGCUGAGCAAGUUGCAAGAAGUUUCUCUGAGGAACUGUGCAGUAAGUUGUGCUGGUGAAAAAGGAGGAGUUGCUGAAGCAUGUCCUAAUAUCAGAAAGGUAGAUUUGUCAAAAAACCUGUUGUCAUCAUGGGAUGAAGUGAUACACAUUGCUGAUCAGCUCAGACACCUGGAAGUCCUUAAUGUCAGUGAAAAUAAACUAAAAUUUCCCUCCGGUUCAGUAUUAACUGGAACGCUUUCUGUACUGAAGGUUUUAGUCCUCAAUCAAACAGGAAUAACGUGGGCUGAGGCUCAUGCGCAGUGUGGUGGCAGCAGGCACGGUCUCGACAUGCAGAAAGACGCCAGCAAGUUCGUGGAUCUGUGCGUGCUGCAGAAAUGCUCCACCAGCAACUGCAUCAUCAGUGCCAAGGACCACACAUCCAUGCGGAUGAACGUGGCCAAGGUGCUGCGGUGUGUCGCGGGGUGCCCAGGCCUGGAGGAACUCUACCUUGAGUCUAACAACAUUUUCAUUUCCGAAAGGCCAACAGAUGUUCUCCAGACAGUCAAGUUAUUAGAUCUUUCCUCUAAUCAAUUAAUUGAUGAAAAUCAGCUGUAUCUGAUAGCCCACCUGCCCAGGUUAGAACAAUUAAUCCUCUCUGACACUGGAAUUUCUUCUCUACAUUUUCCGGAUGCUGGAAUUGGGUGCAAAACGUCCAUGUUCCCAUCCUUGAAGUACCUGGUAGUAAACGACAAUCAGAUAUCACAAUGGUCGUUUUUCAAUGAGCUAGAGAAGUUACCAAGUCUACGGGCUUUGUCCUGCCUAAGAAACCCCCUGACCAAAGAGGACAAAGAAGCAGAGACGGCGCGACUACUCAUUAUCGCCAGCAUUGGCCAGCUGAAGACGCUGAACAAAUGUGAGAUUCUCCCCGAGGAGAGGCGGAGAGCUGAGCUUGACUACCGAAAAGCUUUUGGAAAUGAGUGGAAACAGGCUGGUGGACAUAAGGAUCCGGAAAAAAACAGACUCAGCGAAGAAUUCCUCACAGCCCAUCCCAGAUACCAGUUCCUCUGCCUGAAAUAUGGUGCACCUGAAGAUUGGGAACUCAAAACACAGCAACCACUUAUGCUGAAAAACCAGCUACUAACACUGAAGAUAAAAUACCCUCAUCAACUUGAUCAGAAAGUCCUGGAGAAACAACUGCCGGGCUCCAUGACAAUUCAAAAGGUGAAGGGAUUGCUGUCACGUCUUCUCAAAGUUCCUGUGUCAGACCUUCUGUUGUCCUAUGAAAGUCCCAAAAAGCCGGGCAGAGAAAUCGAGCUGGAAAAUGACCUAAAGUCAUUACAGUUUUAUUCUGUGGAAAAUGGAGAUUGUCUAUUAGUGCGAUGGUGACAACCAACUAAUAAAAUUUAAAGACCACACUGCUUAUCGUGUCUGGGGUUCACCGGAAAUAAAUGAUUCACUGGAACAAUUCUACUGUCAAAACAAAGGGGGUUUACAACUUGUCCUAAGUAUAACAAGGGAUGUAUUUUUUGUUGGGAAGUGACCAUUUCUAGGCUUAUACAUAAUAGCAAUAAUAAAGGCUUUGAACCUACUAAUGAUUUUCUGAUCUUAUUUCAUAUUUAUUUUUACAGCUCAUCACUGCAUUUCAUGAUAAGAUUUAAAUAUUAAAUAGAAAGAAACUAGCUAGCCUAAUAAAAUCUGAACACAGUUAAUAUCUGUCAUAAGACUAGUUUUAAUGGAAUUCUCUAUUGAAACUACUAUUUUAAAGGGUUACUAGAAAUGAUUUGGUUGGUCAUUUUGGGAAAUGUCCCUUAAACUUGGGGAGACAUCCUCUACUAUGUAUAACAAUAUGCUAUUAUCUGUCUUCUCAGUUGCACUAUUUCUAAGAGUACUUAAAUUAAUCACAUGCUUUUCCCUACAAUUAUACCUAAGCUGAGUAUAUCUUCUUCUGUGAUAACCAGCUUUGAUUGAAAUGUACUCAUAUUAGGUAAACAUUAGGCAAUGAUAGGAGGAAAGCAAAACUAAUUCUUUCAAAAUGUCAACAAAAUUUAGAAAUAUCCUUCCCGAUGGCACUAAAACCCUGAGAGGUAUUUGCUUUUAUUCAUACUCACACAACUUUAGCAUUUAAAAACUAUGAGUACUAAACUGUGACCUUCAGGAUUUAUGUUAGAUGGCAGAAAGAAAAUUUGGGUAUUAGUCUACCAUAUAAAUGAACUUCUUUAAAACCAAGGUUCAGAACUGAGAAUCAUAUUGGUUCCUCUUCAAGUUAGUUCAAGUUGCCCACUUCAGAGAUCCACAAAAUCUGACAUUAUUUCCAGAAACCCCAAACUUUGGUAUAAGUGACCACUGCUCAAAUAUGUGAUCACAUGAUCACACAGCAUUCCUGUGAGUUCCUUUUUGUCUGAUAAUUAUCCUAAUUAGCUCUACAGAGCUAUCCUGCAAUCCAGGUUGAAAUUCAAACUCUCAGUUACUACUACAGAUUUCUGAACUAGGCCAAGUUUUAACCAAAAACUAUAGGUAAUGGUGAAUUACUAAUUAGCCACAAUGCAUCAGGAUUUAGAAAUAUUUUUUCUUUUAUAAAAUAACUUGGUAUUUUUCUGAUAAUCUUCCAAUAGAUAAAUAAAAACUUUUCUUAUGCUACAGUACAAGUUGAUUUUUAAGGAAAUUUGUGCAAACAUUAAGAAACACCGCAUUGGUUCUGGGUGAAAGUGCCAGUCUGGAACUCUCUUGAAAGACCAUACAGUCUACUGCUAAACCCUGGGACUCCUCAGACUUGCACUCAGAUUAUCGUUUGCCUGCCCUGAUUUUAGACUCUGCUAAUUCAAGUCCCUGUUAUCUUGCUUGACAUCGACAAGGAUCACCGCACCGUUCCUUCAGUUUCCACAGUUCCGUCAGUUCCCACGGAGAAUACUGAGGAGAAGACAGCAUUCCUGUCUCACAGGUCUUCUCACACAGCCACAGACUGUCCUGUUGAGAAACAACCAAAGCCGAUCUGAGAGUGGUGAAACUGUUUUAAGAGCAUCAGAAAGUAUGCACGUAGACAGCUUUUAUGUAUUCUAAUGAUGCUGAAAUUAUUUCAAGGAUAACUCCGUGUGUGGAACAACUGGUGAGGUUUGGGGGUGGCACCUCCUGAUUUGGGAAAGCACCAGGUCCCACAGUCCUGUGGCUGUGGAAUACAGAAACAAGGCGGUGUGUGGAUGAAGAGUUAGUCAACAAAUGCCAUUCCGUAAUGAACGAUUUUAGAAACCACAAGUGAGUUUCAUGUUUGCUAGUAAAGGUGUGUCUAUGGCAGUAUUAGUAACAGCUAUUAUUCUGAUGGAAUGCUUACAAUAUUGCAGGGACUGUACCAAGUGCUUUGUAAAUAUCUCACUUAAAUCUCACAGUAAUGCUGUGAGGUAGGAACUAUUUCCCUCUUAACAAUUGAGGAACAAACGAAGAGUUAAAAAACUUGUUCCAGGUCACAGGGCUGGUAAAUGAAGAGGAGGGAUUAAAGACUCCCAAGCUCAAGUUCUUAACCACUAGACUAUUUCCUAGCUACGUGAAUUGGUUUCUAUUUCCAGCAAUGUAGCAGAACACAGAGAGAAACUCAUUCAAUGUUUUGACAACACAAAAAUGUUGGAUAAAAUUAAAAACCUUUAUAAAGCAUGGCUCAACUCCGUGAUCAAAGAAGAAACAGGGUAGGAGAAAGCACUGAGUCAGCCUGUGCCUUGAAGGCAGCUGCUGAUCCUUGGGUUUGGAAGGCCAAGCCCAGGGUCAGGAGACUAAUGGGAGACUGACACAGAGCUAGGAUCUCUGAGGGGCCACAGCCUCAGGGGUGAUAAAACAAAACACACUCAGCUUGUCUGUCUCAGUCUUGCCCCUCAGUGGGAUGGAAAGGAGUCUCUCUCCCCUCAGUGCCUACCCACAGCUUGCACUUAGGUAGGUCUGGGGCUGGUAGUCAGUCUGUGUAAGCCCAACAGUUCCAAGCCAAAAAUCUGAAGUAUUCAUAGAUGGUAGUAUUCCUAGAUGCAUGGCAGAAAAAAAUGUAAAUAUGUAAAUCCUCUCUGUAGGAAUGCAUUUUAAAUAGAGGACUCAGUUUCCAAAGACAUGAGAUGGUCACAAAAAAAAAAAAAAAAAAAAGACCGCAUCAGAAAACAAGCGCCAUGAACAACAGUUGUAGAAACAACAAACUGCAAAAUCAGACCCAGCAAAGACUACAGAUCCCAGAAUUACCAGAUACAAAAAAGAAUUAUAUUCAAAGAUGAGACAAAGUACAGCAAAGGAAUCAGACUAUCAAAGUGGACCAUGUAGAUGUGGGUUGAUUUCUUGUCCUGGACUGAGAGCUGCUCUGGGACCCCAGCUCUAUGCAGGGCUUCUAACUGACAGACACUGCAUGUGCCUUCUGUCCCCUGCACCUUCGAUGGCCAAAGUGGAAGCUGCAAGAAUCCAGAACAGAAAUCUCUGAAGCUAAAGCCAGCUUUGUGCUUGAUUUCUUCCCAGGGCUCUAGUUUCCAUUUUGGUCUCUGCAGAUUCAUUUUUUUUUCUGGUUCAGCAAUACUGUGUUUUAAAUGAUGUCUUAUAUUUCAUGCAGUGUCUUAUUUUUAUCGGUCAGAAGGGUUGAAGGAUCCUUAGACUGCCACACUCAAUCAGUGGAUUCUGUCGUUCAGUUUUUUUUUUUGAGACGGAGUCUCGCUCUGUCGCCCAGGCUGGAGUACAGUGGUGUGAUCUUGGCUCACUGCAAGCUCUGCCCCCCGGGUUCAUGCCAUUCUCCUGCCUCAGCCUUCUGAGUAGCUGGGACCACAGGCGCCCGCCACUAUGCCUGGCUAAUUUUUUUUGUAUUUUUAGUAGAGAUGGGGUUUCACCGUGUUAGCCAGGAUGGUCUCCAUCUCCUGACCUCAUGAUCUGCCCGCCUCGGCCUUCUGUUGUUAAGUUUUAAAGCUGCAAAUAAUUUCUGAUCAAAUCUAUGGAAACUGAGUUUUUUUGUAGGCAGGGGAACGUUGAUUUAUAACCUUUUGCUUUAAACUCAGAAAAAUACUGUAUGAGAAAUAACCUAGUGGAUUAUUGUGAAUUAAAGCAACAGCAUAACUAUUA